GAGCCGGAGAGCGAGCGCGGCUGCAGCCGGCGGCAUGGCUAGCACGGCUUCGGAGAUCAUCGCCUUCAUGGUCUCCAUCUCAGGCUGGGUACUGGUGUCCUCCACGCUGCCCACCGACUACUGGAAGGUGUCUACCAUCGACGGCACGGUCAUCACAACCGCCACCUAUUGGGCCAACCUGUGGAAGGCGUGCGUUACCGACUCCACGGGCGUCUCCAACUGCAAGGACUUCCCCUCCAUGCUGGCGCUGGACGGUCUGCAUCCCCGCGGCCCCCGCCCUCAGCCCUCCUUCCUUGAUGGCCAGCCCGCUAGGCGCCCUCUCGCCCCCAAUACCCCCAGCGGGACCCCUAGACUGGACUCCUCUGAGGCCCGACCCGUCUCUCCCAACAGGGCCUUAGGGAGCCAGGGACGCUCCUGGUGCCCGCCCUCUCCUGAUGGCUGUCUCGCGGGGCGCCUGUUCGAGCCUGGGACCCCGGGAGGGGGGACACGCAGACAGGCCCGGGUUGGUGACUCCCAGGCGUCGGGGGAUGGGGAAGCUUUGCGGUCCUGAGAGUCAAGGAAGCGGCUGCCCUCCCCCACCCCCCAUAUCUUGGGGACCGCUGGGACCCAGAGUUCAUGCUGCAGGGGCUUGUCUCCUCCACCUCCCUCCCCUACGUUCCCCGAAGGCUGGGUUCUGAUAAAAAUGGUGUCAUUGCAAGCCAAAUCCGUUUGUCCUGACCUCCCUUGAGCCAUUUCGUUGGUUCUUUUAAAAGUAGGCGGGGGUGGGGGUUGAGAGGUUGGAAGCGGGAAAACAUAUUGCAGAAUUUGUUGUUGUUAUUGUUUCCCUUUAAAGAGCUUCUACAAACUUGUCUGCCUAGGCAACACUACAAACACUUCCUCCGAGUUUUAGGAAAAUAAUAGCCCUUGCGGUGCCGCGAUGAGUCCGCAGAGGGUAGGGAAUCUUGGGCCGUGAGAGCGUGGCGCCGGGAGCUGACCAGUUCUGCAUCCGAGUCCCCGGUGCCUGCUGCUGUCCUGGGUUGUUCCUUUGUGGAGGUUCACCUGCGUUGCUCUGGUUAGUCAGGCCUUAUGCUGGUAGCAGCUGGUGGAUAUUCACACAGAACUCUGGCUCUGUUGAGUUUCAAGACAACAGCCGAUGUCAGCCCGGUCCCAUUGAUUGCUCAAGUUCUAGGCCCGUUGCUUCCAGGAUUUUACAGCAAACGAAUCCUGGCAGAAACUUAAGAGGAGUUAUUUACAUUACAUAUUUCUAGAUUUGAGGUGUUUUUUUCUUUUAUUACCGCACUUGCAGGUUUUGUUUACAUAGCUGGGUAAAUGAAAGAAAAUAGUUGAUUCCUCUAAGAUGGGGUUUGCCACGAAGAGCAAACUGUUGCUCAACGUGGUAUUUGAUGGAACCUCCGUAUAAGGAAUACGCAUCUAGUUUUAGAAGGGUGGCGCCCGGGUCCGUGUCCUGUUCGGUAAAAUAAGCAGCCGGAACAGUGUUUAUUCCCCAGCAUUACCGUUGAAUUUCCUGUGGUUUGUAGAGCACGCAUCCAGGUAGAUGAACAGGCAUUCUCUUGUUCCUGUGAUUUAUAGUCAGCAAUGUGUUACUGUCCUCUGAACACUCUUCUGUUGUAACUCUAUUGUUCUCUGAGAUAGUGUGCCAGAUAGGUACGCUUCCUUCUGUAGGACAGUUGGGGGACAAGGGAGAGAAGGAAAUGAAUGCUCUAUGAAUAUUAUUAAGUGCAGAAUAAUAAAGUUUUCUCCUACAUGUCUGCAGUGAGAGUGGAGGUGGUACCAUACCUGUUUGGGGGCAGAUCGGGCCGGGAGUGAAGAGGAAGUAGGAAUAGUUGUCCUGGUUAGCUGGGAGGAGAACAGAGAGGAGUGACAUUUUUAUGCCAUCCAGCUUGCAAAAUGGCCUUCCUGUGUGCUCAUGUGACUAAAAAAUGACUUUUAAAAACAUAAAUGGCAUGACACUACCUACUGUUGUACAACACUUUAAAAUCAAUGUAUUUUUCCAAGUCAGUACUUAAUAGAAGUGACUUGACUCUGUGUAACUGCUGCAUGGUAUAUUCAUUAGACUGCAUAAAAUGGCUUAGUUAACCAUAGAUCCAUUGUGGACAUUGGACCUUUUCCAGCUUUUCUUUGUUGGUGGUGCUUUACUGAAAAUCUUAUAUUCACCUCUUUGUAUGUGUGUGUAUUUCUGUAGACUCCAUUCCACUGAGAAAUGGUAUCGUAAGAGCAGUAGAAUACACGUGCAUUUUAAUAUUCAGUUCAUACUGUCAAAUUACUUUCCACUGACAGUGUAUGAGAAUACCUGCUUCUCCACAUUCUCACCACUCUGUGUUAAUCCAGUUUUUUUUUUUUUUUUUUUUGAGACGGAGUUUUGCUCUUGUUGCCUAGGCUGGAGUGCAGUGGCACAAUCUCAGCCGACUGCAACCUCCGCCUCCCAGGUACAAGUGAUUCUCCUGUCUCAGCCUCCCAAGUAGCUGGGAUUACAGGCAUGUGCCACCAUGCCCGGCUAAUUUUUUUUGCAUUUAGUAGAGACAGGGUUUCACCAUGUUAGGCUGAUCGCGAACUCCUGAACUCAGGUCAUCCACCCUCCUCGGCCUCCCAAAGUGCCGGGAUUACAGGUGUGCGCCACCGCGCCCAGCCAUCUUAUCAUUUUAGUUGGCAUUUCCCUUAUUGCCGUGGUCAAAAUCACUGGUUAUAAAAAUGGUCAAAACUCACUGACCGUUUUUUUUUCUCUUUUGUGAAUUGGCAUCCAUAUCUUAGGCCCAUGGUUCUGUUGUUUCUUUGUGGUUUCGAUGAUUUGUCAGUCCUUGAUUUGUUAUGUAGGUUGCAAUCUCACACCAUUGUUCAUCUUUUAAAUUUAUGAUGCCUUUUCUCACACAGGACUUUGAAAUUUGUAAUAGAAUCAUAUUUAUCAGCCUGUUUUUUUGAUGACUUUCCUUCUGUGGCUUAAGAUGGCAUUUCUUACCGCAAAACAAACUUACUUUUCUGUAUCUCUCAGAAUAACAUCUUGGAGGGUUAAAUCAUGCAACUGUGUUUUCCUGUGGAGGGGAGUUGAUUCCCCCACCUGCAAGUGGAAGCUUCCAGGGUAGGGGCCCUCUGUUUGUCCUCUACCUUGCAUUCCCAGGUCAGCCACAUCUGGUGGGUGCUGGUCCUGACAUUGCCUUUGGAGAAAGUGGCCAUGGUGGCCUGAGUGGAACAGCCCUCCCCUUAAACCCAGGGGAGUUUAUCCCCUGCUCUUUGCUCUCCAUUUCAGAAAAUCUGGCCAAUGAUCGUCCUUGUAAAUUGCCUUCUUUGUGCAUGCGCAAAAUUAACAAGUUAUGGCUGCUGUUCAUGCUGGAGAAAGGUUAUAUACAGGCAUGUAGAGGACUUAUGAUCGCUGCUGUCAGCCUGGGCUUCUUUGGUUCCAUAUUUGCGCUCUUUGGAAUGAAGUGUACCAAAGUCGGAGGCUCCGAUAAAGCCAAAGCUAAAAUUGCUUGUUUGGCUGGGAUUGUAUUCAUACUGUCAGGGCUGUGCUCAAUGACUGGAUGUUCCCUAUAUGCAAACAAAAUCACAACGGAAUUCUUUGAUCCUCUCUUUGUUGAGCAAAAGUAUGAAUUAGGAGCCGCUCUGUUUAUUGGAUGGGCAGGAGCCUCACUGUGCAUAAUUGGUGGUGUCAUAUUUUGCUUUUCAAUAUCUGACAACAACAAAACACCCAGAUACACAUACAACGGGGCCACAUCUGUCAUGUCUUCUCGGACAAAGUAUCAUGGUGGAGAAGAUUUUAAAACAACAAACCCUUCAAAACAGUUUGAUAAAAAUGCUUAUGUCUAAAAGAGCUCGCUGGCAAGCUGCCUCUUGAGUUUGUUAUAAAAGCGAACUGUUCACAAAAUGAUCCCAUCAAGGCCCUCCCAUAAUUAACACUCAAAACUAUUUUUAAAAUAUGCAUUUGAAGCAUCUGUUGAUUGUAUGGAUGUAAGUGUUCUUACAUAGUUAGUUAUAUACUAAUCAUUUUCUGUUGUGGCUUUCUAUAAAAAAUAAACAGUUUAUUUACAGGAUUUGUAAAAUGUUUUCUACAUUUAUAUAGAACAUGAAAAGCAUUUAGUACCAAAGGUUCAAGAAGUAUUCGUACUCUAGCCUUUUUAAUCAUUCAUAGAUAGAAGUCUUUGUACCCACUCCUUAUGUUUCUUUUCAUUCAUAAACAGGUGUAUAAGGAACAAUGUCUUAUAAACAGCAUGGGGGCAAUCUGAGAAUAUUCCUCAAAAGGUGUCCAGGUUAAAUAGACAUGUUACUGGCUGCACACAGGCAAAUUCUAGUUUGUUUUUUUUAAGUAUUCUACAACAUUUAUUUAAAAAGGUAAAUCUUUUUGUUGAAGCAGCAAGUUAUCUGGUAGAACUUAACUUCUACAGGAUCAGAGAGGAUCUUGCUCAUUCAUGGCCAUAUCCACAUGCCCAUGGCCACUCAGUAGAUUGUUGAAAAAGCAAAGCCACACCAUUCUCUUUGAUGUAUGCAGAGAGUUACGUAGCAGGGGAUGUUCUCUGAUUUAUUCCACUGGCACCAUUAGUGAAUAUUUAGUUGUUUUCAUAAACGAUGCUGUGAUGAAGACUCAUGUACAUAUUUAGCAAAUUUUGGUUUCUUACAUGUGCCUGUCAUGACUGUAAUUCAUUAUGACUGCUCCAGGAAGGGCUAAUGGGGCCAAUAUAUUAUUGCCUGUCAUGUGGCACAUCCAUGUUAAGGGGCUGAGGCGUCCCUGGCACGGAAUGCAGAGCCCUGAGCUAGGGCAUCAGCAGAAGCUGAGAUAGAGAUAUUGGUCAUGGUUGACUGAGGAGCCAAUUAAAACCUGUUUAUGCCUAGUGUUCCAUUAUUGGAACACUAAGCAUGUGGGAGUUAUUUAUAUCCUACUGCUCAAGGUCAUCGCCAAGGUGUGAUUGGAAAAAUUCAAAAAAUUGCAACCUCAGGCAUAAAUGGGUUAAGGACAUCCCAAGCCCAAGUGGUACGUGCCUCACUCAGAACUGACGGGCCGAGUUCUAUCUAGGUGUGUCUUCCAGAACCUGUUUACGGCUAACUGGAUAACUGAGAGACUUGUCAUUUCUAAAGACAUUUAAGUUGCUCCAGGGAUUUCUGAAAAAAGACACAGGCUUCUUCCUAGAGCCAGCCCUAUAUAACAUGCCCACAAGGGCAACAGUUAUCACAGUUCAUACACACCUUUCAUGUCCUGUCUCACUCACUCCUCACAGCCAUCCUAGGAGAUACAUAUUGUUUUCAUCCUGCAUUUACAGAAAAAGAAAUGAAAACAGAGAGCUUAAAUAAUUUGCCACAGUAAUGUCGAAACUAGGCCUUUGAACCAAGGCAGUCUAGGGUAAAAUAUAGUUUCAAAGUAUGAAUAAGAAUUGGUAUUUGUGUUAUCUUUGAGUAAGAAACUGUCCGAUAUGAAUCACAACGUGGGUGAAUGUAGUAUUUUCCUGAAGUGUGAAAGACUUAAAAAAAAGAAUCACAUUGUUCAGAGGUGCUCAAUGGAAAGAAAAGGAAAUGAACAAGUUUGUUAAAAGAUAAAAAAUAAAAAAAAUUCCAUACCUUGA